GUCCUCGCAGCCAUGGCGGCCGCCGCGCUCCCAGCAUGGCUGUCUCUGCAGUCGAGGGCAAGGACUCUGCGUGCAUUCUCCACUGCCGUCUACUCGGCCACUCCGGUCCCGACACCUAGCCUGCCGGAAAGAACACCCGGAAAUGAAAGGCCACCAAGAAGAAAGGCACUACCUCCUAGGACAGAGAAAAUGGCUGUUGACCAGGACUGGCCUAGUGUUUACCCAGUUGCAGCACCAUUUAAACCCUCUGCAGUACCUCUUCCUGUUCGAAUGGGUUAUCCAGUAAAAAAGGGCGUGCCCAUGGCAAAGGAGGGAAAUCUAGAACUUUUAAAGAUUCCCAAUUUUCUGCAUUUGACUCCUGUAGCAAUUAAAAAGCACUGUGAAGCCCUUAAAGAUUUUUGCACUGAGUGGCCAGCCGCACUGGACAGUGACGAGAAAUGUGAGAAGCAUUUUCCAAUUGAAAUUGACAGCACUGAUUAUGUUUCAUCAGGACCAUCUGUUCGGAACCCCAGAGCACGAGUAGUAGUCUUAAGAGAAAUGUAAAAAAAUAUAAUCCCAGCAGAAUGUGAGAAGGCCUGCUUUCCUGUGCUCUCACCAACCUACAUAUUACCUGUCAACUUGAUAGGUAAAAAAUUUGUCUUAUAUUUAAAAUUUGUAUGUCUUUGAAUACUAGUGAGGUUGAGGAUUUAUUCCUUUGCAAAACAUGUAUUUUUUGUCAUUUGCUCAUUUUGGUGGUGUAUUGAUUCCUUGUAUACCUUUUUUUUUUUUUUUUUUUUUUUUUGAGACAGGGUCUUACCCUGUCACCCAGGCUGAAGUGCAGUGGCGCGAUCUUGGCUCACUGCAGUCUCUUCCAUCCGGGCUCAAGUGAUUCUCCCAUCUCAGCCUCCUGAGCAGUAGCUGGAACUGCAGGAGUGUGCCACCAUGCCUGGCCAAUUUUUUUGAAUUUUUGUAGAGACAGGGUUUUGCCAUGAUGCCCAGGCUGGUCUCAAAUUCCUGGACUCAGGCGAUCUGCCUGCCUUGGGCUCCCAAAGUGCUGGGAUUACAGAUGUGAGCCACCACUACAGGGCCGUUGUUUCUUUUUAAUAAUGGCUUUAUUGAGACAUAGUUCACUUGCUAUAGAAUUCCCCCCUUAACCAUCCUCAAGCCCCUUUUAGCCACUAAUCUACUUUUUGUCUCUGGAUUUACCUAUUCUUGAUGUGUUACAGAAAUGGAACCAUGCAAUAUGUUUUCUUUCACUUAGUGUAAUGUUUUCAAUAGGUUUCAUCUGUUGUAGCAUGUAUUAUUUUAUCAUUUCUUUUUAUUGCCAAAUAUUUUAUUUUAUGAAUAUACCACAUUUUAUUUAUCCAUUCAUUAAUUGGUGGACAUUUGGGUUGUGUCUACUUUUUGGAUGAAUAAUGCUGUUGAACAUUCACAUACAGGUUUUUGUGUAGAUAUGUGUUUUCCAUUCUCUUGGGUAUAUACCUAGCAGUGGAAUGACUGAGUUGCAUGGCACCUCCAUAUUUAACAUUUUGAGGAACUGCCAAACUGUUUUUGAAAAACAAUUUCAAAGUGGCUUCACUAUUUUACAAUUUCACCAGCAAGUUUGAGGCUUUCUAUUUCUCCACAUCCUCACUAAUGGUUAUUACCUGUCCUUUAGUUUUAGCCAUUCUGAUAGGUAUGAAAGUAUCAUUGUAGUUUUGAUUUGUGUCUCCCUAAUAACCAUCUUUUCAUGUGCUUGUUGACUAUUUGUAUAUGUUUGGAGAAAUGUCUGUUCAUAUCCUUUGCCUGUUUUUUAAUUGGGUUGUUUAUCUUUCGAUUGUUGAGUUAUAAGUGUAUUUUAUAUAUUCUGGACACCAGUCCCAGUCCCUUCUCAGAUAUAUGAUUUGUAAACAUUUUCUUCCAUUCUUUGGGUUGUCCUCUUACUUUCUUGAUGAUGUCCUUUUUUUUUUUUUUUUUUGAGACGGAGUCUCACUCUGUCACCCAGGCUGGAGUGCAGUGGCUCGAUCUCAGCUCACUGCAAGCUCCGCCUCCUGGGUUCACAGCAUUCUCCUGCCUCAGCCUCCCGAGUAGCUAGAACUACAGGCACCCGCCACCACGCCUGGCUAAUUUUUUGUAUUUUUAGUAGAGAUGGGGUUUUCACCGUGUUAGCCAGGAUGGUCUCGAUCUCCUGACCUUGUGAUCUGCCUGCCUCAGCCUCCCAAAAUGCUGGGAUUAGAGGCGUGAGCCUUUUAAGCACAGAAGUUUUAAUUUUGAUGAAGUCCAAUUUAUGUAAGUCAUGUGCUGCAUAAUGAUGUUGUGGUCAGUGAUAAACACAUACACAACAGUGGUCCCAAGAGAUUAUAAUACUGUAUUUUCACUGCACUUUUUCUAUGUUUAGAUAUGUUUAAAUACACAAGUACAAUUUUGUUACAGUUGUUACAGUAUUUAACAGUAACAUGCUACACAGGUUUGUAGCCAAGGAGCAAUUGACUAUACCAUGUAGUCUAGGUGUGUAGUAGGCUGUACCACCUAGGAUUGUGUAAAUACAUAAUGAUGUUUGUACAUGACAAAAUCACCUAGCCAUGUCUUUGUCAAAAAAUAUUGUUAAGUGGCGUAUGACAGUAUUUUUCCUUUUGUUUCUUGUGCUUUUGGUGUCAUAUGUAAGAAAUCAUUGUCUUAUUCAAGGUCAUAAAAGAUUCACUCUUGUGUUUCCUCCUAAAAGUUUUAUAGUUUUAGCUCUUACAUUUAGAUCUAUGACCUAUUGUUUGUUAAUUAUCAUACAGUUGUUCCUCAGUAUCUGUUUGGGAUUGGUUCCAGGAACGCUUGUAAAUUCAUAGAUCUGUGGAUGCCUAAGUCCCUGAUAUAAAAUGGCAUAGUAUUUGAAUAUUGAAUAUAACCUAGUACAUCCUCCUAUAUACUUUGUCAUUUCUAGAUUACUUAUAAUGCCUAAUACAACGUAAAUAGUUGUUAUACUGUAUUUUAAGAAUAUGCAGUUUAAAAAUUGUUAUAUUGUUAUUUUUUCUGAAUAUUUUCAAUCCACGUUCCAAUCCACGGUUAGUUGAAUCCACAAAUGUGGAGCCCGUGGAGACAAAGGGCUAACUGGAUAUGGUGUGAAGCUGGGGUCCAGCUUCAUUCUUUUGCAUUCCGUUUGCAUGUUGAUCCAAUACCAUUUUUGAAAAGACUAUUCUUUCCCAUUGAAUGGUCUUGACAUCCUUGUCAAAAGUCAUAUAGUUAUCUUUUAACUUUUCAUUUGGCUACUUUACCAAAUUCUCUUUUUUAAAUUUUUUAUUAUGAAAAUUUUCAAAUGUAUGGACAAGUAGAAAGAGGCUAAUAUAAUAAAUACCCAUACACAUGGCAUCUUGAUUUAGUAAUUAAUAUUUUGACAAAUUUGCUUCAUACACAUACAUACACAUCUAAGUACCUUAACAUUUCUGACACCUAAUGUUUCACACUAAAAUACUUCAGUGUGUUAUCUCUAAGAAUUAAGGAGAUGUUUCCUAUUUAAUUCCAAUACUAUUACCACAUGUAACAAAAUUGUCAGUAAUUCCCAAAUAUCAUCUAAAAUAUCUACUCCACAUUAUAUUUCCCCUAUUGCCUUACAAAAUGGUAUUUUUUAAGCUCUGUUAUUGAAACCAGAAUCCCGCCAAAGACCAUUGUAUUUGGUAAUGAUGUAUCUUAUGUUAUCUGGAAUGGCAAACAACCCCACCUCCCUCCCUUCUUCCUGAUGAAUUUGACUUGUUAAAGAGACAGGGUAUUUAUCUUGUAACAUUUCCUAUCUUCUGAAUUUGCCCCAUUGCAUCUGGAUGUCAUUUACCUUAUUUCUUUAUCUCCUGUAUUUCACAUAACCUGGAAGUUAGAUUUAAAGGGCUGAUAAGAUUCCAGUUAAAUAUGUUUGGCAAGAAUACUUUAUAGAUAUUGCUAUGUAUUUUAUAUUGCAUCAGGGGCACGUAAAGUCUGGUGGCCUCAUUCUCAGUAUGCUGAAAUUGAGCACUUGGCUAAGAAGCUGACAACCUAAUCAUUCCUUUGUGAAGAUUUUUGUUUUGCUUUUCCCUUGAACAAGUAAUCUGUGGGUGGAUAUCAAGUAAAAUCAUUAUUCUUUUUGGUCCUCGAAGUAUAUCUAUCUUACCUUUGGCCAGUGGGAACUCUUUUAAGUUGGUUCCUGUGUCCUUUUGUUACAAUCCUUUAGCAUUUGAAAGUUUCCUUGUAUUUUGACACAAGAUGGUUCAGGCUCAUUUUUAUAAAUUUCUUAUCCCGGACCUGGAAUCAGCCAUUUUUCAAGGAGCCCUAAUACCUGCCAGUGGACAGUGGUGUUUACAGACCAUGAUCUGGAUGCUAGGACUUCUCAGCUGAUUCUUUCGGAAAUUUCUCAAGACAUAAUAGAUAAAUAAUGGUAGUUUUAAUUCCCCUUUUCAAGUAACCAUAGCUUGUUUUUUCUUUUUGUCUUUUGCAUUAGAUAAAAUUUCUGAAGUCAUAUUUCUGUAGUUCCUUAUGCUGUUGCAUACUUUAAUUGUCUGUGCCUCUAGUGUUUAACCUCAAGUAUGAGGUAGGAUUUCAGUGAGAUAAUAGUGUUUAUUAUGUUAAUGGUGUAUCCUAUUCUUAGAUUACUAGCAUUUAUGAAAUUACCUCCUUUGAAUUAUUGAAGUCAUAAAUUACAUCAAUAGGUUUUCAAUAUACUGAUGCAUUUCUGAACCCUGGUCAGUUCAUAGUGUAUCAUUCUUUUAUUCUACUGCUGAUUUGCUGUGCUAGAAUUUUACUUAGGGUCAUUUGUCCGGAUGCCAUAUUGCUUUGGAGAAACAUGAGAUCCCUACUGUUACUCACCUGGACCACGCCACGUGCCAUUGCACUUCCAAGUGUCUGCCCUAGGAACUUCUAAUUUAGUAUUUGAAGUCACUGUUUGUUUCCUUUGUCAAAGAAAUCUUGGUACACAUGGCAUAUCUUUUUCACACAGCAGUCAUGGAGCAGUUACCUGAUAUACUUUUUAAAAUUAAACUUUUUAUUUUAGAAUAGUUUUUAGUUUACAGAAAGGUUCCAAGAAUAGUAGAGAAUUUCAGACCCAGGUUCCCCUGUUGUAAACAUCUUAAAAUAUACUAUGGUACGUUUGUCACAACUAGUGAAUUAAUAUUGAUACUGAAUCAAUAUUGAAUUUAUUGUUAUUAAAGUCCCUACUUUGUUCAGAUUAUCUUAGUUUUUUUCUAAUACCCUUUUUCUGUUCCAGAAUCCCAUCCAGUUUACAAAUCACAUUUAGUCAUCAUAAUUUCUUAGGUUUAUCUUGGGUGUGAUGUUUCUCAGACUUGACUUGUUUUUGAUGACCUUAACAGUUUUGAGAAGUACUAGUUGUAUAUUUGGUAGAAUGUCUUUCAACUUGUUGUGUGUUUGGGGAGAAAAACCCCAGAAAUAAAGUGCCAUUCUCAUCACAUCAUAUCGAGAGUAUAGGCUAUUAAGAUGAUUUGUUUUGUUUGUUUUUUUGAGAUAGUGUCUCAUUCUGUCACUUACGCUGGAGUGCAGUGGCACAAGCACGGCUCACUGCAGCCUCGACCUUCCCAGGCUCUGGUGAUCCUCCCACCUUUGUUUCCCCAGUAGCUGGGACUACAAGCGCAAGCCACCACGGCUAGCUAGUUUUCGUAUUUUUUGUAGAGAUGAGGUUUUGCCAUGUUGCCAGGGGGUUUUGCCAUGUUGCCAGGGCUGGUCUGGAACUCCUGGGCUCAAGUGAUACUCUCACCUCAGCCUCCUAAAGUGCUGGGAUUACAGGCAGUGAGCCACUGUGCCGGCCAUGAUUUGUCAGUGAUGAUGCUAAUCUUCAUCACCUGGCUGAGGUAGUACUUGUCCAUUUUCUUCACCAUAAAAUUAUACUUCCUCCCCUCUUACCCAUACUCUACUCUUUAGAAGAAAGUUACUAUGCAGAGCCCACACUUAAGGAUCAGGAGGUAUGCUCCACUUCUUUGAGAAAGAAGUAUCACAUAAAUUAUGUACAGUCCUUUUAUAUGGCAAAUUUGUUCAUUCUCCCCUAUUUAUUAAUCAUUUAUUUAUAUCAGUAUGGACUCAUGGAUAUUUAUUUUACACUAUGUGUCAUAAUCCAAUAAAACAUUAUUUUUUUGCUCAAAUUGUUCUGAGUUUAACCAUUGGGAACUCUUUCCAGUGACUCUUCUGUUCCUUUGCCAUGCCCCUGUCAUUUGUUUUUAAGCAAUUUCUUAUUUUCUGGCACUACAAAAUGCUCUGGGCUCUUUCCCUGUCCCAUUCCUAGAAUCAGCAUUUCUCCAAGGAGCCCUUACUGAUGUGCUUUUGAUUUGUCUGGAGGGUGACUACUACCUCUUUGAGGUGCCUCCUGGGACCCUCAAAAUAUUAACUUUUAUACUCUGUGUAGCCUGUACUUUAAGCCAGAACAUUCAAAGUACACUGAAGAAAUGUGUUGAAAAUCUAUGCAACCAUUUUCGCAUUAUGUACUAGCAAAUAAACAAUCUUUAAUUUCUGGAAUUUUCCAUUUUCCUCAGUGAUAUUGUUGAUUGAUUUGUAGUUUUCUUUCUUUGCUAGGUUUCAGUAUCAGGGCUGUACCAAUUUUUUUCUUAAUUUAAUAUAACUUUAUUUUUUUGAGACAGGGUCUCGCUCUGUUGCCCAGGCUGGAGUCCAGUGGCGCGAUCUUGGCUUACUGCAACCUCUGCCUCCAUGGUUCAAGCGAUUCUCCUGCUUCAGCCUCCCAAGUAGUUGGAAUUAUAGGAAUGCUCCACCACACCCAGCUAAUUUUUGUAUUUUUAGUAGAGAUGGGGUUUCACCAUGUUGGCCAGGCUGGUCUUGAACACCUGACCUCAAGCGUUCCUCCCUCCUUGGCCUCCCAAAGUGCUGGGAUUACAGGUGUGAGCCACCGCACCUGGCCUGUGCCAUCUUUAUGAAGUGAAUUAUGAAGCUUUCCAAUCUUUUUUAUUUUGUAGAACAGUUUAAAUACACAACAAUAUACUAAGUUCUUAGAUUGAAGCUGUUUUUAAAUCACAAAGACAGUAUAUGUUUACUGUAUAAAAUUUCAAAAAUCCCAAUAAAAGAAAAAAAAGAAUUGAAAGUUCAGCCAUGCUUGUACCAUUCCACAGGUUCAUAUUUUUAAGAACAUAUUAAAUGUUACCUAUUUUUCAUAAUAAUGGUAACAACUACAACCAACAGUUGUUGAGCUCUGUUGUGUGUUGAAAAAUCUCUGAACUGAGAGUCAGAAAACCUAGAUCUUAAUUUACGUUAUUCACCUCAAGUUUUGUGGGCCUCCGUCUUCAGUCCUAGAAUUGACAUCCAAUGUCCCUACUGGUUCUAAGUUUGCUUAUUUUAUUUCACACAAAAAUAAUCUCAUUGCUUUAUUUGAAGGAUGGCACCAGAUUUCAUUUCUUGUAUCAUGCUUUUCCUCUUGUCCUCUCUGUGCCUUGUGCUAGCCUGUGAUGCCUUCAUUGCUCCCUUGUACCCCUUCUGCUGACUUCAUGUCUGCCCUGCUAGACUCUGCACCCCACCUGCUGGCUGUUGAGGCUCAGUGGUGGUGUCCUGGAUGUGCCAUGUAGUUCAAGGGUAAACGUAGGUCAAACAGGUGGACUAAAGCACAUGCAGUCCAGCAUGAUUAAAGCAAUAUCGUGAAGGUAGUCAACUGUUAGAAACUACUAUUGGACAUACUCAAAUGUUUUAAUGCACAGAAAAAAAAAUUUUGAUAGUCAUAAAAGUUUAGGAUUAAAAACAACUUAUAUAUAACUUUACUUCAAAAGUGCUUUAUUCUAUUAAUCUCAUUUAUUUCUGACAAAAAUUCUGGAAUUAAGUGUUCUUGAGGAAACUGAGUCUCAGGGAGGUAACAUGAUUUAAGGUAACAUUAAAUGGCAAAUCUACAAAUCAAA